GGCCCGUCUGGGAAACGGCUAUUCCAGUGAGACUUUGGGUGAGCGCCUCAACCUCUCUGCCGUUGCCCAGUGUGACCGAGACCAGAGGUGAGGCCCCCCACCCAGGGGAGAGGAAGGCCAGAGGUGCUGGAGAUGAGGGGAUGCUCCAGGCAGAGGCACAGUCCCUCACCCCACAGCAACCAGUGAGCACAUACCCCAGCAGGCUGCGCUUGGGGCUGGGGCACAGAUGGGCACAGUGCUGUCCUGUGGAACCUACGGUCCAGGGAGGGAGCUCGUGGGGCUGAUGUACAGACUGGGUAGGGAAGUGGUUGAGGAUGAAGAAGAAAUACAUUAAAUGCCAGGAAUUCUCAAUGGCCAUGUCCAUCCAGCCCAAGGUUCUUCCCCAAGCUCCACAGGAGUUCUGGACCAUGUGAAAUCCAAAGUUAACCAACGUGGAAAUCUCGGCAUUUCCCCAAGUCCAGCUCUUCCUCUACUUCUGGAAUCUAUUCUCCACGCAGCUGCAGUGAUCUUUUAACAACCUGAACUCGGGUCUAUCACUUCUAUUGACACCCCCUGCACUUCCCACUACAUUCAGACCAUCACUGGGACAUCACUGGGACGGCCUGAGCUGGCCAGAUCCCUCACUGCUUUCCUGCUCCCUACCGCCCACGGAUUUAUAGCAUCAGUGUUCCCUCCUUCGGAAAGCCUUCCCGCCAGCAGGAAGCAGGCGCCUGCUAUCAUUCCACAUCCCAGCCAGGGGAGGGAAAGGGCAAGACCCUGCAGGAAUGGCCAGCUAAGGAAAGGGAACGACCGGAUCAGAUCAGAGCUCUAAAAAAGAUGGGGAACGUUAUAAAGUGGAGGGGAGAAGCGGCCUCCUUCCACUUAGGACAGUGGUCCAAGCCAGAGCGGAAAGGCAGGGGAGUAGGAUGAAUGGGACAGAAAGUGAAAUGACCAGAGCAGAGUCUCAAAGCGCGUGCCCUCAACCAGGUGCAAGUCCUGCAAGCCCCCGAGGGAAGGAAAGGGGGCAGCUAUCAGGGCACACCCCACCCCAAACCGCCUAACAGGAAUUUCUGCGGUGGUUUCCAGGAAGGAAGCAGCCACCCUCGCCAUGGCCUCCCCGCCCGCCUGCCCCUCGGAGGAGGACGAGAGCCUGAAGGGCUGUGAGCUGUACGUGCAGCUGCACGGGAUCCAGCAGGUCCUCAAAGACUGUAUCGUCCACCUCUGCAUCUCCAAGCCCGAACGCCCCAUGAAGUUCCUCCGGGAGCACUUCGAGAAGCUGGAGAAGGAAGAAAACAGGCAGAUUUUGGCGCGGCAAAAGUCAAACUCACAGUCGGACUCCCAUGAUGAGGAGGUGUCGCCCACCCCCCCGAACCCUGUGGUGAAGGCCCGCCGCCGGCGAGGAGGCGUGAGUGCCGAGGUGUACACCGAGGAGGACGCCGUGUCCUACGUCAGGAAGGUGAUUCCCAAGGACUACAAAACCAUGACUGCGCUGGCCAAGGCCAUCUCCAAGAACGUGCUCUUCGCUCACCUGGAUGACAACGAGAGGAGUGACAUAUUCGAUGCCAUGUUCCCUGUCACUCACAUCGCUGGGGAGACUGUUAUACAGCAAGGGAAUGAAGGAGACAACUUCUAUGUCGUUGAUCAAGGGGAAGUGGAUGUGUACGUGAACGGAGAGUGGGUGACCAACAUCAGCGAGGGAGGCAGCUUCGGGGAGCUGGCGCUCAUCUACGGCACCCCCAGGGCUGCGACCGUGAAAGCCAAGACGGACCUCAAGCUCUGGGGGAUCGACCGGGACAGCUACCGGCGCAUCCUUAUGGGCAGCACGCUGAGGAAACGCAAGAUGUACGAGGAGUUCCUCAGCAAGGUCUCCAUCCUAGAGUCCCUGGAGAAGUGGGAGCGUCUGACCGUGGCGGAUGCGCUGGAGCCCGUCCAGUUUGAAGAUGGAGAGAAAAUUGUGGUCCAGGGAGAGCCUGGGGACGACUUUUACAUCAUCACGGAGGGCACCGCGUCCGUGCUGCAGCGCCGGUCCCCCAAUGAGGAGUACGUGGAGGUGGGGCGCCUGGGACCCUCUGACUACUUCGGGGAGAUUGCACUGCUGCUGAACCGGCCCCGGGCGGCCACUGUCGUGGCCCGGGGGCCCCUCAAGUGUGUGAAGCUGGACCGGCCCCGCUUCGAGCGUGUGCUGGGGCCCUGCUCUGAGAUCCUCAAGAGGAACAUUCAGCGUUACAACAGCUUCAUCUCCCUCACCGUCUGAGCACAGCUCCCGCCCUGCAGCCCCAGCUCCCCAGUGUGGUGGCCGUGCCCUGCUCGUCUGUGUCGGGGGCCCGGGAGCCGCUGUGUGAGGUGUGGGCCGGGUGGGGCUGGGUCCCGGCAGCGUGAGGACUGCCCCUUCCCCGGACUCACUUUUUGGAAUAAAUGAUCACCUUGUGCAUUUCCAAAUCAAAGGACAAGCGGACAAAAUGCAUCCCAAGAUCAAGGAAGGGACAGGCCAGCUUCCUCCCCACACGCCUCCCCGGCUGCCUCUGUGGGCUUCUCCUGGGGGGCCCACCCCACCCCUGCCAGUCUCCUGGAGAUGCUUGAGGAUCGGUCCUCCCCAGAACCAGGCCAGGACGUUGCCCCUGGGGCCUGGUGACCCUGUGAGGUCAGGUCCCCCAGAUUGAGGUCUGAGUGUGGGCAAGUGUGUCAAAAGGGGCUGCCCCCCAGGGGAGAUGAGGCUGAGAGCAGGGAGUUGAGGCCGAAGAAGUCAAGGCCCCUCCCGCAAAUGUGUACCCCUGCCCGCGCCACUGCACCCCGCCGCACCCCCACCUCCCCCGGGGGCCCUGCUGCGGAUGCCGGAGUGGGAGAGUCUCUGAGCUGUGAGAUUGAUCUUGCCCCUAAUUGGAGAGGAAGCCGGGCGCCAAGACACACGGGGCUCCUGCCUUGGGAGCCAGGGCCGCGGCCGCAGGUAGACCCCAGUAGGGGGGGCCGGGCUCGAAGUUCCUUUGGGAGGGGCUGGCGGGACUCCAGCAGGCCGUCCUCACCUUUCUUAGAAAGUCCACCCAGGGCAAGUUGAUGUUGGGGGAAAGCAGAAGUCAAGCCAGCCGCGGGCCCCACACGCCCCGACCCGCUCAACCGACUUGUCCCUUAAAUGUGUCUUGGAUCCCGCAGUGAUGACGUGAGCCAGCCAGGCCCGAAAGGGUGAGGCCAGUGCAGAGAAGCUUCCCAGGGGAUUCCUGGGUUCCCCCGAAAGACAAGCGAGGUCAUUGCAGUUCACCUGAUGUUGCUCCUGUCCCGUGCGUCCCGGGGAGGCUGUCCUUGGUCCGAGGCUGCUCGUUGCAGCCCCUCCCCUGCUGGCGGUUACGAUGCGUGGGGUCCCCCUCCCCACCCAGCCCCGGCCACGUCGCCGUGUCCCGCCUGUGCCUGUGACGUCCCUGUGGACCUGUGAGCCAUCCCCCCCCUUAUCUCUGCUCUGAAUACUGCAUGAAGCAUUAAACGUGCAAUGAAGUAC